GUAGAGAAGCAGAAGGAAGCAAGAUGGCUGCCCUUUAGGAUUUGUUAGAAAGGAGACCCGACUGCAACUGCUGGAUUGCUGCAAGGCUGAGGGACGAGAACGAGAUUGCAUUAUUCAUUUUCAUAUGCCUGCCUUUAUCUGCUUUGGAAGCCUAUUUCCUAAUCUUCCAAGAUUUAUCAUCACCUUCAUAUGUCCAUAGCAUGCAUUUCUCAGACAGGCUGGCAAACAUUCAGCAGCACACCCUCUCAAGAUUGUUUACUUGCCUUUGCUCCUGUUGAGUUACAACGCUUGGAAGCAGGAGAUGGGCUCAGCAGCAGCCAAUAGGACAUGAUCCAGGAAGAGCAGUAAGGGACUGAGCUGCUGAAUUCAACUAGAGGGCAGCCUUGUGGAUGGCCCCGAAGCAAGCCUGAUGGAACAGGAUAGAACCAACCAUGUUGAGGGCAACAGACUAAGUCCAUUCCUGAUACCAUCACCUCCCAUUUGCCAGACAGAACCUCUGGCUACAAAGCUCCAGAAUGGAAGCCCACUGCCUGAGAGAGCUCAUCCAGAAGUAAAUGGAGACACCAAGUGGCACUCUUUCAAAAGUUAUUAUGGAAUACCCUGUAUGAAGGGAAGCCAGAAUAGUCGUGUGAGUCCUGACUUUACACAAGAAAGUAGAGGGUAUUCCAAGUGUUUGCAAAAUGGAGGAAUAAAACGCACAGUUAGUGAACCUUCUCUCUCUGGGCUCCUUCAGAUCAAGAAAUUGAAACAAGACCAAAAGGCUAAUGGAGAAAGACGUAACUUCGGGGUAAGCCAAGAAAGAAAUCCAGGUGAAAGCAGUCAACCAAAUGUCUCCGAUUUGAGUGAUAAGAAAGAAUCUGUGAGUUCUGUAGCCCAAGAAAAUGCAGUUAAAGAUUUCACCAGUUUUUCAACACAUAACUGCAGUGGGCCUGAAAAUCCAGAGCUUCAGAUUCUGAAUGAGCAGGAGGGGAAAAGUGCUAAUUACCAUGACAAGAACAUUGUAUUACUUAAAAACAAGGCAGUGCUAAUGCCUAAUGGUGCUACAGUUUCUGCCUCUUCCGUGGAACACACACAUGGUGAACUCCUGGAAAAAACACUGUCUCAAUAUUAUCCAGAUUGUGUUUCCAUUGCGGUGCAGAAAACCACAUCUCACAUAAAUGCCAUUAACAGUCAGGCUACUAAUGAGUUGUCCUGUGAGAUCACUCACCCAUCGCAUACCUCAGGGCAGAUCAAUUCCGCACAGACCUCUAACUCUGAGCUGCCUCCAAAGCCAGCUGCAGUGGUGAGUGAGGCCUGUGAUGCUGAUGAUGCUGAUAAUGCCAGUAAACUAGCUGCAAUGCUAAAUACCUGUUCCUUUCAGAAACCAGAACAACUACAACAACAAAAAUCAGUUUUUGAGAUAUGCCCAUCUCCUGCAGAAAAUAACAUCCAGGGAACCACAAAGCUAGCGUCUGGUGAAGAAUUCUGUUCAGGUUCCAGCAGCAAUUUGCAAGCUCCUGGUGGCAGCUCUGAACGGUAUUUAAAACAAAAUGAAAUGAAUGGUGCUUACUUCAAGCAAAGCUCAGUGUUCACUAAGGAUUCCUUUUCUGCCACUACCACACCACCACCACCAUCACAAUUGCUUCUUUCUCCCCCUCCUCCUCUUCCACAGGUUCCUCAGCUUCCUUCAGAAGGAAAAAGCACUCUGAAUGGUGGAGUUUUAGAAGAACACCACCACUACCCCAACCAAAGUAACACAACACUUUUAAGGGAAGUGAAAAUAGAGGGUAAACCUGAGGCACCACCUUCCCAGAGUCCUAAUCCAUCUACACAUGUAUGCAGCCCUUCUCCGAUGCUUUCUGAAAGGCCUCAGAAUAAUUGUGUGAACAGGAAUGACAUACAGACUGCAGGGACAAUGACUGUUCCAUUGUGUUCUGAGAAAACAAGACCAAUGUCAGAACACCUCAAGCAUAACCCACCAAUUUUUGGUAGCAGUGGAGAGCUACAGGACAACUGCCAGCAGUUGAUGAGAAACAAAGAGCAAGAGAUUCUGAAGGGUCGAGACAAGGAGCAAACACGAGAUCUUGUGCCCCCAACACAGCACUAUCUGAAACCAGGAUGGAUUGAAUUGAAGGCCCCUCGUUUUCACCAAGCGGAAUCCCAUCUAAAACGUAAUGAGGCAUCACUGCCAUCAAUUCUUCAGUAUCAACCCAAUCUCUCCAAUCAAAUGACCUCCAAACAAUACACUGGAAAUUCCAACAUGCCUGGGGGGCUCCCAAGGCAAGCUUACACCCAGAAAACAACACAGCUGGAGCACAAGUCACAAAUGUACCAAGUUGAAAUGAAUCAAGGGCAGUCCCAAGGUACAGUGGACCAACAUCUCCAGUUCCAAAAACCCUCACACCAGGUGCACUUCUCCAAAACAGACCAUUUACCAAAAGCUCAUGUGCAGUCACUGUGUGGCACUAGAUUUCAUUUUCAACAAAGAGCAGAUUCCCAAACUGAAAAACUUAUGUCCCCAGUGUUGAAACAGCACUUGAAUCAACAGGCUUCAGAGACUGAGCCAUUUUCAAACUCACACCUUUUGCAACAUAAGCCUCAUAAACAGGCAGCACAAACACAACCAUCCCAGAGUUCACAUCUCCCUCAAAACCAGCAACAGCAGCAAAAAUUACAAAUAAAGAAUAAAGAGGAAAUACUCCAGACUUUUCCUCACCCCCAAAGCAACAAUGAUCAGCAAAGAGAAGGAUCAUUCUUUGGCCAGACUAAAGUGGAAGAAUGUUUUCAUGGUGAAAAUCAGUAUUCAAAAUCAAGCGAGUUCGAGACUCAUAAUGUCCAAAUGGGACUGGAGGAAGUACAGAAUAUAAAUCGUAGAAAUUCCCCUUAUAGUCAGACCAUGAAAUCAAGUGCAUGCAAAAUACAGGUUUCUUGUUCAAACAAUACACACCUAGUUUCAGAGAAUAAAGAACAGACUACACAUCCUGAACUUUUUGCAGGAAACAAGACCCAAAACUUGCAUCACAUGCAAUAUUUUCCAAAUAAUGUGAUCCCAAAGCAAGAUCUUCUUCACAGGUGCUUUCAAGAACAGGAGCAGAAGUCACAACAAGCUUCAGUUCUACAGGGAUAUAAAAAUAGAAACCAAGAUAUGUCUGGUCAACAAGCUGCGCAACUUGCUCAGCAAAGGUACUUGAUACAUAACCAUGCAAAUGUUUUUCCUGUGCCUGACCAGGGAGGAAGUCACACUCAGACCCCUCCCCAGAAGGACACUCAAAAGCAUGCUGCUCUAAGGUGGCAUCUCUUACAGAAGCAAGAACAGCAGCAAACACAGCAACCCCAAACUGAGUCUUGCCAUAGUCAGAUGCACAGGCCAAUUAAGGUGGAACCUGGAUGCAAGCCACAUGCCUGUAUGCACACAGCACCACCAGAAAACAAAACAUGGAAAAAGGUAACUAAGCAAGAGAAUCCACCUGCAAGCUGUGAUAAUGUGCAGCAAAAGAGCAUCAUUGAGACCAUGGAGCAGCAUCUGAAGCAGUUUCACGCCAAGUCGUUAUUUGACCAUAAGGCUCUUACUCUCAAAUCACAGAAGCAAGUAAAAGUUGAAAUGUCAGGGCCAGUCACAGUUUUGACUAGACAAACCACUGCUGCAGAACUUGAUAGCCACACCCCAGCUUUAGAGCAGCAAACAACUUCUUCAGAAAAGACACCAACCAAAAGAACAGCUGCUUCUGUUCUCAAUAAUUUUAUAGAGUCACCUUCCAAAUUACUAGAUACUCCUAUAAAAAAUUUAUUGGAUACACCUGUCAAGACUCAAUAUGAUUUCCCAUCUUGCAGAUGUGUAGAGCAAAUUAUUGAAAAAGAUGAAGGUCCUUUUUAUACCCAUCUAGGAGCAGGUCCUAAUGUGGCAGCUAUUAGAGAAAUCAUGGAAGAAAGGUUUGGACAGAAGGGUAAAGCUAUUAGGAUUGAAAGAGUCAUCUAUACUGGUAAAGAAGGCAAAAGUUCUCAGGGAUGUCCUAUUGCUAAGUGGGUGGUUCGCAGAAGCAGCAGUGAAGAGAAGCUACUGUGUUUGGUGCGGGAGCGAGCUGGCCACACCUGUGAGGCUGCAGUGAUUGUGAUUCUCAUCCUGGUGUGGGAAGGAAUCCCGCUGUCUCUGGCUGACAAACUCUACUCGGAGCUUACCGAGACGCUGAGGAAAUACGGCACGCUCACCAAUCGCCGGUGUGCCUUGAAUGAAGAGAGAACUUGCGCCUGUCAGGGGCUGGAUCCAGAAACCUGUGGUGCCUCCUUCUCUUUUGGUUGUUCAUGGAGCAUGUACUACAAUGGAUGUAAGUUUGCCAGAAGCAAGAUCCCAAGGAAGUUUAAGCUGCUUGGGGAUGACCCAAAAGAGGAAGAGAAACUGGAGUCUCAUUUGCAAAACCUGUCCACUCUUAUGGCACCAACAUAUAAGAAACUUGCACCUGAUGCAUAUAAUAAUCAGAUUGAAUAUGAACACAGAGCACCAGAGUGCCGUCUGGGUCUGAAGGAAGGCCGUCCAUUCUCAGGGGUCACUGCAUGUUUGGACUUCUGUGCUCAUGCCCACAGAGACUUGCACAACAUGCAGAAUGGCAGCACAUUGGUAUGCACUCUCACUAGAGAAGACAAUCGAGAAUUUGGAGGAAAACCUGAGGAUGAGCAGCUUCACGUUCUGCCUUUAUACAAAGUCUCUGACGUGGAUGAGUUUGGGAGUGUGGAAGCUCAGGAGGAGAAAAAACGGAGUGGUGCCAUUCAGGUACUGAGUUCUUUUCGGCGAAAAGUCAGGAUGUUAGCAGAGCCAGUCAAGACUUGCCGACAAAGGAAACUAGAAGCCAAGAAAGCUGCAGCUGAAAAGCUUUCCUCCCUGGAGAACAGCUCAAAUAAAAAUGAAAAGGAAAAGUCAGCCCCAUCACGUACAAAACAAACUGAAAACGCAAGCCAGGCUAAACAGUUGGCAGAACUUUUGCGACUUUCAGGACCAGUCAUGCAGCAGUCCCAGCAGCCCCAGCCUCUACAGAAGCAGCCACCACAGCCCCAGCAGCAGCAGAGACCCCAGCAGCAGCAGCCACAUCACCCUCAGACAGAGUCUGUCAACUCUUAUUCUGCUUCUGGAUCCACCAAUCCAUACAUGAGACGGCCCAAUCCAGUUAGUCCUUAUCCAAACUCUUCACACACUUCAGAUAUCUAUGGAAGCACCAGCCCUAUGAACUUCUAUUCCACCUCAUCUCAAGCUGCAGGUUCAUAUUUGAAUUCUUCUAAUCCCAUGAACCCUUACCCUGGGCUUUUGAAUCAGAAUACCCAAUAUCCAUCAUAUCAAUGCAAUGGAAACCUAUCAGUGGACAACUGCUCCCCAUAUCUGGGUUCCUAUUCUCCCCAGUCUCAGCCGAUGGAUCUGUAUAGGUAUCCAAGCCAAGACCCUCUGUCUAAGCUCAGUCUACCACCCAUCCAUACACUUUACCAGCCAAGGUUUGGAAAUAGCCAGAGUUUUACAUCUAAAUACUUAGGUUAUGGAAACCAAAAUAUGCAGGGAGAUGGUUUCAGCAGUUGUACCAUUAGACCAAAUGUACAUCAUGUAGGGAAAUUGCCUCCUUAUCCCACUCAUGAGAUGGAUGGCCACUUCAUGGGAGCCACCUCUAGAUUACCACCCAAUCUGAGCAAUCCAAACAUGGACUAUAAAAAUGGUGAACAUCAUUCACCUUCUCACAUAAUCCAUAACUACAGUGCAGCUCCGGGCAUGUUCAACAGCUCUCUUCAUGCCCUGCAUCUCCAAAACAAGGAGAAUGACAUGCUUUCCCACACAGCUAAUGGGUUAUCAAAGAUGCUUCCAGCUCUUAACCAUGAUAGAACUGCUUGUGUCCAAGGAGGCUUACACAAAUUAAGUGAUGCUAAUGGUCAGGAAAAGCAGCCAUUGGCACUAGUCCAGGGUGUGGCUUCUGGUGCAGAGGACAACGAUGAGGUCUGGUCAGACAGCGAGCAGAGCUUUCUGGAUCCUGACAUUGGGGGAGUGGCCGUGGCUCCAACUCAUGGGUCAAUUCUCAUUGAGUGUGCAAAGCGUGAGCUGCAUGCCACAACCCCUUUAAAGAAUCCCAAUAGGAAUCACCCCACCAGGAUCUCCCUCGUCUUUUACCAGCAUAAGAGCAUGAAUGAGCCAAAACAUGGCUUGGCUCUUUGGGAAGCCAAAAUGGCUGAAAAAGCCCGUGAGAAAGAGGAAGAGUGUGAAAAGUAUGGCCCAGACUAUGUGCCUCAGAAAUCCCAUGGCAAAAAAGUGAAACGGGAGCCUGCUGAGCCACAUGAAACUUCAGAGCCCACUUACCUGCGUUUCAUCAAGUCUCUUGCCGAAAGGACCAUGUCCGUGACCACAGACUCCACAGUAACUACAUCUCCAUAUGCCUUCACUCGGGUCACAGGGCCUUACAACAGAUAUAUAUGAUAUCACCCCCUUUUGUUGGUUACCUCACUUGAAAAGACCACAACCAACCUGUCAGUAGUAUAGUUCUCAUGACGUGGGCAGUGGGGAAAGGUCACAGUAUUCAUGACAAAUGUGGUGGGAAAAACCUCAGCUCACCAGCAACAAAAGAGGUUAUCUUACCAUAGCACUUAAUUUUCACUGGCUCCCAAGUGGUCACAGAUGGCAUCUAGGAAAAGACCAAAGCAUUCUAUGCAAAAAGAAGGUGGGGAAGAAAGUGUUCCGCAAUUUACAUUUUUAAACACUGGUUCUAUUAUUGGACGAGAUGAUAUGUAAAUGUGAUCCCCCCCCCCCGCUUACAACUCUACACAUCUGUGACCACUUUUAAUAAUAUCAAGUUUGCAUAGUCAUGGAACACAAAUCAAACAAGUACUGUAGUAUUACAGUGACAGGAAUCUUAAAAUACCAUCUGGUGCUGAAUAUAUGAUGUACUGAAAUACUGGAAUUAUGGCUUUUUGAAAUGCAGUUUUUACUGUAAUCUUAACUUUUAUUUAUCAAAAUAGCUACAGGAAACAUGAAUAGCAGGAAAACACUGAAUUUGUUUGGAUGUUCUAAGAAAUGGUGCUAAGAAAAUGGUGUCUUUAAUAGCUAAAAAUUUAAUGCCUUUAUAUCAUCAAGAUGCUAUCAGUGUACUCCAGUGCCCUUGAAUAAUAGGGGUACCUUUUCAUUCAAGUUUUUAUCAUAAUUACCUAUUCUUACACAAGCUUAGUUUUUAAAAUGUGGACAUUUUAAAGGCCUCUGGAUUUUGCUCAUCCAGUGAAGUCCUUGUAGGACAAUAAACGUAUAUAUGUACAUAUAUACACAAACAUGUAUAUGUGCACACACAUGUAUAUGUAUAAAUAUUUUAAAUGGUGUUUUAGAAGCACUUUGUCUACCUAAGCUUUGACAACUUGAACAAUGCUAAGGUACUGAGAUGUUUAAAAAACAAGUUUACUUUCAUUUUAGAAUGCAAAGUUGAUUUUUUUAAGGAAACAAAGAAAGCUUUUAAAAUAUUUUUGCUUUUAGCCAUGCAUCUGCUGAUGAGCAAUUGUGUCCAUUUUUAACACAGCCAGUUAAAUCCACCAUGGGGCUUACUGGAUUCAAGGGAAUACGUUAGUCCACAAAACAUGUUUUCUGGUGCUCAUCUCACAUGCUAUACUGUAAAACAGUUUUAUACAAAAUUGUAUGACAAGUUCAUUGCUCAAAAAUGUACAGUUUUAAGAAUUUUCUAUUAACUGCAGGUAAUAAUUAGCUGCAUGCUGCAGACUCAACAAAGCUAGUUCACUGAAGCCUAUGCUAUUUUAUGGAUCAUAGGCUCUUCAGAGAACUGAAUGGCAGUCUGCCUUUGUGUUGAUAAUUAUGUACAUUGUGACGUUGUCAUUUCUUAGCUUAAGUGUCCUCUUUAACAAGAGGAUUGAGCAGACUGAUGCCUGCAUAAGAUGAAUAAACAGGGUUAGUUCCAUGUGAAUCUGUCAGUUAAAAAGAAACAAAAACAGGCAGCUGGUUUGCUGUGGUGGUUUUAAAUCAUUAAUUUGUAUAAAGAAGUGAAAGAGUUGUAUAGUAAAUUAAAUUGUAAACAAAACUUUUUUAAUGCAAUGCUUUAGUAUUUUAGUACUGUAAAAAAAUUAAAUAUAUACAUAUAUAUAUAUAUAUAUAUAUAUAUAUAUAUGAGUUUGAAGCAGAAUUCACAUCAUGAUGGUGCUACUCAGCCUGCUACAAAUAUAUCAUAAUGUGAGCUAAGAAUUCAUUAAAUGUUUGAGUGAUGUUCCUACUUGUCAUAUACCUCAACACUAGUUUGGCAAUAGGAUAUUGAACUGAGAGUGAAAGCAUUGUGUACCAUCAUUUUUUUCCAAGUCCUUUUUUUUAUUGUUAAAAAAAAAAGCAUACCUUUUUUCAAUACUUGAUUUCUUAGCAAGUAUAACUUGAACUUCAACCUUUUUGUUCUAAAAAUUCAGGGAUAUUUCAGCUCAUGCUCUCCCUAUGCCAACAUGUCACCUGUGUUUAUGUAAAAUUGUUGUAGGUUAAUAAAUAUAUUCUUUGUCAGGGAUUUAACCCUUUUAUUUUGAAUCCCUUCUAUUUUACUUGUACAUGUGCUGAUGUAACUAAAACUAAUUUUGUAAAUCUGUUGGCUCUUUUUAUUGUAAAGAAAAGCAUUUUAAAAGUUUGAGGAAUCUUUUGACUGUUUCAAGCAGGAAAAAAAAAUUACAUGAAAAUAGAAUGCACUGAGUUGAUAAAGGGAAAAAUUGUAAGGCAGGAGUUUGGCAAGUGGCUGUUGGCCAGAGACUUACUUGUAACUCUCUAAAUGAAGUUUUUUUGAUCCUGUAAUCACUGAAGGUACAUACUCCAUGUGGACUUCCCUUAAACAGGCAAACACCUACAGGUAUGGUGUGCAACAGAUUGUACAAUUACAUUUUGGCCUAAAUACAUUUUUGCUUACUAGUAUUUAAAAUAAAUUCUUAAUCAGAGGAGGCCUUUGGGUUUUAUUGGUCAAAUCUUUGUAAGCUGGCUUUUGUCUUUUUAAAAAAUUUCUUGAAUUUGUGGUUGUGUCCAAUUUGCAAACAUUUCCAAAAAUGUUUGCUUUGCUUACAAACCACAUGAUUUUAAUGUUUUUUGUAUACCAUAAUAUCUAGCCCCAAACAUUUGAUUACUACAUGUGCAUUGGUGAUUUUGAUCAUCCAUUCUUAAUAUUUGAUUUCUGUGUCACCUACUGUCAUUUGUUAAACUGCUGGCCAACAAGAACAGGAAGUAUAGUUUGGGGGGUUGGGGAGAGUUUACAUAAGGAAGAGAAGAAAUUGAGUGGCAUAUUGUAAAUAUCAGAUCUAUAAUUGUAAAUAUAAAACCUGCCUCAGUUAGAAUGAAUGGAAAGCAGAUCUACAAUUUGCUAAUAUAGGAAUAUCAGGUUGACUAUAUAGCCAUACUUGAAAAUGCUUCUGAGUGGUGUCAACUUUACUUGAAUGAAUUUUUCAUCUUGAUUGACGCACAGUGAUGUACAGUUCACUUCUGAAGCUAGUGGUUAACUUGUGUAGGAAACUUUUGCAGUUUGACACUAAGAUAACUUCUGUGUGCAUUUUUCUAUGCUUUUUUAAAAACUAGUUUCAUUUCAUUUUCAUGAGAUGUUUGGUUUAUAAGAUCUGAGGAUGGUUAUAAAUACUGUAAGUAUUGUAAUGUUAUGAAUGCAGGUUAUUUGAAAGCUGUUUAUUAUUAUAUCAUUCCUGAUAAUGCUAUGUGAGUGUUUUUAAUAAAAUUUAUAUUUAUUUAAUGCACUCUAA